AGUAGACUCUAUUAUUUCAAGAAAGAUGGCGUGGAUAAACUGUUAGAUGCUGCUCAGAAACACAAUAGAACAUGGACAGAGAAGUGACUUGGGAUAAAUCGUGUUCCUGUCUAUCUCUUACUCUGGGACCACCACUGAGCUCGAGACUGCCAGACACUUCUUUCUAAACUCAGCACCCAGCAAAGGACCUGGCACAUAAUAAGUGCUCUGGUUGUACAUGGAGGAUGACCGAAAAAACCAAUGGUGUGAAGAGCUCCCCAGCCAAUAAUCACAACCAUCAUGCACCUCCUGCCAUCAAGGCCAAUGGCAAAGAUGACCACAGGACAAGCAGCAGGCCACACUCUGCAGCUGACGAUGACACCUCCUCAGAACUGCAGAGGCUGGCAGACGUGGAUGCCCCACAGCAGGGAAGGAGUGGCUUCCGCAGGAUAGUUCGCCUGGUGGGGAUCAUCAGAGAAUGGGCCAACAAGAAUUUCCGAGAGGAGGAACCUAGGCCUGACUCAUUCCUCGAGCGUUUUCGUGGGCCUGAACUCCAGACUGUGACCACACAGGAGGGGGAUGGCAAAGGCGACAAGGAUGGCGAGGACAAAGGCACCAAGAAGAAAUUUGAACUAUUUGUCUUGGACCCAGCUGGGGAUUGGUACUACUGCUGGCUAUUUGUCAUUGCCAUGCCCGUCCUUUACAACUGGUGCCUGCUGGUGGCCAGAGCCUGCUUCAGUGACCUACAGAAAGGCUACUACCUGGUGUGGCUGGUGCUGGAUUAUGUCUCAGAUGUGGUCUACAUUGCGGACCUCUUCAUCCGAUUGCGCACAGGUUUCCUGGAGCAGGGGCUGCUGGUCAAAGAUACCAAGAAACUGCGAGACAACUACAUCCACACCCUGCAGUUCAAGCUGGAUGUGGCUUCCAUCAUCCCCACUGACCUGAUCUAUUUUGCUGUGGACAUCCACAGCCCUGAGGUGCGCUUCAACCGCCUGCUGCACUUUGCCCGCAUGUUUGAGUUCUUUGACCGGACAGAGACACGCACCAACUACCCUAACAUCUUCCGCAUCAGCAACCUUGUCCUCUACAUCUUGGUCAUCAUCCACUGGAAUGCCUGCAUCUAUUAUGCCAUCUCCAAAUCCAUAGGCUUUGGGGUCGACACCUGGGUUUACCCAAACAUCACUGACCCUGAGUAUGGCUACCUGGCUAGGGAAUACAUCUAUUGCCUUUACUGGUCCACACUGACUCUCACUACCAUUGGGGAGACACCACCCCCUGUAAAGGAUGAGGAGUACCUAUUUGUCAUCUUUGACUUCCUGAUUGGCGUCCUCAUCUUUGCCACCAUCGUGGGAAAUGUGGGCUCCAUGAUCUCCAACAUGAAUGCCACCCGGGCAGAGUUCCAGGCUAAGAUCGAUGCCGUGAAACACUACAUGCAGUUCCGAAAGGUCAGCAAGGGGAUGGAAGCCAAGGUCAUUAGGUGGUUUGACUACUUGUGGACCAAUAAGAAGACAGUGGAUGAGCGAGAAAUUCUCAAGAAUCUGCCAGCCAAGCUCAGGGCUGAGAUAGCCAUCAAUGUCCACUUGUCCACACUCAAGAAAGUGCGCAUCUUCCAUGAUUGUGAGGCUGGCCUGCUGGUAGAGCUGGUACUGAAACUCCGUCCUCAGGUCUUCAGUCCUGGGGAUUACAUUUGCCGCAAAGGGGACAUCGGCAAGGAGAUGUACAUCAUUAAGGAGGGCAAACUGGCAGUGGUGGCUGAUGAUGGUGUGACUCAGUAUGCUCUGCUGUCGGCUGGAAGCUGCUUUGGCGAGAUCAGUAUCCUUAACAUUAAGGGCAGUAAAAUGGGCAAUCGACGCACAGCUAAUAUCCGCAGCCUGGGCUACUCAGAUCUCUUCUGCUUGUCCAAGGAUGAUCUUAUGGAAGCUGUGACUGAGUACCCUGAUGCCAAGAAAGUCCUAGAAGAGAGGGGUCGGGAGAUCCUCAUGAAGGAGGGACUGCUGGAUGAGAACGAAGUGGCAACCAGCAUGGAGGUCGACGUGCAGGAGAAGCUAGGGCAGCUGGAGACCAACAUGGAAACCUUGUACACUCGCUUUGGCCGCCUGCUGGCUGAGUACACGGGGGCCCAGCAGAAGCUCAAGCAGCGCAUCACAGUUCUGGAAACCAAGAUGAAACAGAACAAUGAAGAUGACUACCUGUCUGAUGGGAUGAACAGCCCUGAGCUGGCUGCUGCUGACGAGCCAUAAGACCUGGGGCCCAACUGCCUCUCCAGCAUUGGCCUUGGCCUUGAUCCCAGAAGCUAGAGGAGCUAUUUAGAUCUCCGGAUUUACAUGCAUUACCCUCAUGUUCCCUGAAUUCUCCCAAAAGCCUCUCUGACCCUGGGUUUUUGGCCUAAACAUCCAAGAUUCCGCCUCCAAGUUUAGCCCAAGUUUGUGGAGAGUACAGACUGCGUUGGCUGGGCUUCCGAGAGCUUCGGCCUGCCUAAGUCUGAGGAAGGGAGAAGGGGGCAGCUGUCUGCCAGGAGUCUGGCUCUUUUGCUCAUAGCGACCCCUCCCUUGGUUCUGGCCCCCGCUUUUUCUAACAUGUCUUCUGAAUGCUUCCUUUUUCCCUGCACACGCAUGUACUUCGAGCACCGACUAUAGACAUUUAGAUCAGGUACCCAGUGUCUGUCUCCCACGACAGGCCAAGGGAUGUGAUAGUGUUGUUGGGAGGGGGUAGAAGGGUGCCCACUCAGGGUUAUUCCUCCCCCAUCAGAUGCUCCAGCUCCUGCUCUGUAGAUUGAUCUGUCUGUCUGCUAGCCAGGAUGGGAUCUCUGCAGUCUUCUGUGGACCAAGGAGAUAGACCCGGCUUCUGGUCCAUUCCAGGGCAGGGAGUGAGGAGCAAGGCAACUGGCAUUUGUCCACCUGGAGACAGAGGUAGCUGGCAGCUCUGGCCAUCCCUCCCCUAUGAAGAGCAUUCCUAAAGAGGCCCUGAAAACUGCUGGUGGUGGGGAGACUCUUCAAGUUAAUAUCUGCAUUAGAGGCACCUAUGAGUUAAAAAAUUCCUUUGAACUAUCUGUGGUUAUUGCUCAACUCUGCUGUUCACAUUCUCUCCCUCCCUUCAUUAAUCCCUCUCUUUUCACCAUAUGGUUGUCCCUCAGUAUUCAUCAGGGAUUGCUUUCAGGAGUCCCCAUGGAUACCAAAAUUUGUGGAUGUUCAAGUCCCUGAUACAAAAUGACGUCGUAUUUGAAUAUAACCUAUGCACAUCCUCCCAUACUUUAAGUCAUCUCUCGAUUAUUUGUAACACCUAAUACAAUGUCAGUGCUAUGUAAAU